AAGUGCUCGCUGCAGCUUCCCGGAGCCGGAGCGCAGCGCCUGCGGCCGCCCGUGCCCCGCCGUCCUCCUUCCCGCGGCCGUGAGGGAGACCGCGGCUCGGCCGUAGCGGAGCUGCGAGUUACAGAAUGUCUGAAGGGGACAGUGUGGGAGAAUCCGUCCAUGGGAAACCUUCGGUGGUGUACAGAUUUUUCACAAGACUUGGACAGAUUUAUCAGUCCUGGCUAGACAAGUCCACACCCUACACGGCUGUGCGAUGGGUCGUGACACUGGGCCUGAGCUUUGUCUACAUGAUUCGAGUUUACCUGCUGCAGGGUUGGUACAUUGUGACCUAUGCCUUGGGGAUCUACCAUCUAAAUCUUUUCAUAGCUUUUCUUUCUCCCAAAGUGGAUCCUUCCUUAAUGGAAGACUCAGAUGACGGUCCUUCGCUACCCACCAAACAGAACGAGGAAUUCCGCCCCUUCAUUCGAAGGCUCCCAGAGUUUAAAUUUUGGCAUGCGGCUACCAAGGGCAUCCUUGUGGCUAUGGUCUGUACUUUCUUCGACGCUUUCAACGUCCCGGUGUUCUGGCCGAUUCUGGUGAUGUACUUCAUCAUGCUCUUCUGUAUCACGAUGAAGAGGCAAAUCAAGCACAUGAUUAAGUACCGGUACAUCCCGUUCACACAUGGGAAGAGAAGGUACAGAGGCAAGGAGGAUGCCGGCAAGGCCUUCGCCAGCUAGAAGCGGGACUGAGGCUGCCUCACGUGUUGCAAGAACAGUUUUGAGCCAUUGUUAACAAUGCCUUUUUUCUUCACAUAAAGUAGUUGAUUACGAGGGAGUCAAAUUUUCUUUUUAAAAAGGAGCUUCAAUGAUUUGUAACUGAAAUAUCAGGUUCUAGAAGAAACUGGCGCUUAAACCAAAUCGCAUGGAUUUCUUUUUCAGUGACGUUCAAGUGUUUCUCACGGAUGGAAUUCUAGUCAGCUGCAGGCGGGAAGCCAGGCGGGUGGAGCCCAUGGGAGCAAGGGCGAGUGGCCGGUCCCCGCUGUGCCAGGUGGGCAGGCAGGAGCAAGGCCUGCGAGGGAGGAACGGGCCGCUCCCCGCCAGCCGCCUUCCCCAGCAGCCGCAGGUGGUGCCAGCCACUCCACAGAGCCCGAGGGAUGAUCUAGCCUGAUUCCUGCGUGUCCGAAAGAACUUAACGUUUUAAAGGUGAUUGUCAAGUAACUGUGUGGGGUUCUAAUGCCAGUUUCCUAAUUCCAUCUCACUGGAGAUGUUUAAAGUUGGCCUCUAUCCUAAUGACUCAAAACUUGGUUCUUAACUACCAUGAUUGCUUUUGAGGGCCCGGAAUUAUAAAUAUAUAUUAUAUUUUAAUUGUUUGAGAUUAUUUUGACACAUUUCUUUGAUACGUAGAGUGUUUUGUUUUUAAUUUAAAUCUGUCCUCAUGCAACCCUCCAUGAGGGGCAGCGAAGCUGGCAGGGAGCAGACUGGCUUUGUAGGUUCAGCACUCGGCCCCCCACUGCGGGAGAGGCGGAACCCACUUGCAUGUCAGCGUUUUUGAUUCGAGAAAAGAAAUACUCUCAACGUUUUACCAAGUGAUUUUACCUCCACCUUUACUAAAGUCUUUACCUAAAACAUGGCAGUCGCUGGACACAGGAAAGCCCACCUUUUGUUUGGCCUUUUCGAAAGGUGACCCAUAUUGCACAGCAGAACAUCACAGCUGUGGUCCCAGAUGAGACACUGACAUGCGAGUGAAGGCCUCUCCUCCUGGGCCCCGGGCUGCGCAGGCUCCUCACUCUGGGCGGUGUUUCCUGUCUCAGAAUUGACACGGUGAAUGCUUAGUGUCUGGAUUUUCUUGUACCAGUGUUUACAUAUCUGACAUCGAGCUCCUCUAAGAGGCCACGUUCAAGCUUGUGUGUCCCUGACCCAAGAUAGCCAGUGCUGCUCCCAGGUGGUACUUCUGGUACCGUGUUGAGACACUUGGGAUUCUCAGACUGUGGACAGGAGUGUUUGUCAUUUUUCAUACUGUUUUCUUAAUAAGCGCUCAGGCCUAAGGUGUGACAGGAAGUCGCACGCGCUUGGCCAGAGCACAGUGAAGCAAAGGACUGGGUGCUGAUGGAUGGAGCCACGGCGGCAUCUGCCCACCCGGCCGCAGCCCCCAGUGCCUCUCCUGGUGGUCCUCCCAGUCUAGAGGGUCACGGCCCCCCCGCCCUCCUCCGUCUCUGGCAAGCUGACCUUGACUAACCCAGGAAUACAGGGUCAUCCUCAUUCCUAAGUAAGUCAAACAGCAAGACAUGGUUUGCGCGGGUCUUUGCCGGAAGCCGGUCCUGCUGGCCAGGUGUUUUACGUCAGCAGGGAAAUGUGGCACACGCCCUCGAGGCAUUUUAACACUGCGCUUCAGGAAAUCUCAAGUUCCAUCUUGUGUUAGUAACGUACCCACAUUUUGCUGGAGUUAGUUUAUUAAAGAUGCCUACGGUGAACUCUCUGGCGCAGGUUAAAUGCAGUUUUGAAAACCUGGAAACAUCAAAUGGAGGCGGGAAAUAGGCUGGGGCCGAGCUGAGGGGCUGAACACAGCAGUGACCGUGGGUCAGCAGGUCGCCUGCCCAGCAGGCCCCCCAGGAGAGGGCUCGGGCGCCCCUGGCAGCCCCCAUACCCCCAGGACCUGGCUCGUGAGUGCGUCUGGGUCAGGAAGAGACCUCUCUGUGCGUCUCAGGCUGAGAUGCAGAUUUCUGUUUUCUAAAACUGGAAGCGACCUUGACGUGUAUUGAAGGUGUGUGUGCCAAAUGCUUCCGACGGAGGUGCUGGCCUUGGUUGGUUUCUCUCUGCCCCGUGUGGUCAUCAAGUCCUGGGGGAUGUGCUCUGCCCAGCCGCCCUCGGGGAGAGCAGCGCCGCCUCCCAUGGGGCCGUGGGGCUGCUGUUCUCACUGCACUGGCUGAAGCAACCCGCCAGCCUCCGUGCCCCACCCCACCCAGCACGCACUCAUUCAGUCCAUUGCCUUAACACAAGCCUGAUGGGGCUGUUUUCUCACAAUAUAAACGAAUAAAGUGUCUUCUGGCCUA